AGGGAGAGGUGAUAUCCAGCCUCAGUUGGACAGUGCUCUCCAAGAUGUCAAUGAUAAGUAUCUCUUAUUGGAAGAAACAGAAAAGCAGGCUGUCCGGAAGGCUUUGAUUGAAGAACGUGGCCGAUUCUGUACCUUCAUCUCUAUGCUGCGGCCAGUGAUUGAAGAAGAAAUCUCAAUGCUAGGGGAAAUAACCCACCUUCAGACCAUCUCGGAAGAUCUAAAAAGCCUGACCAUGGACCCUCACAAACUGCCCUCCUCAAGUGAACAGGUGAUUCUGGACUUGAAAGGUUCUGAUUACAGCUGGUCGUAUCAGACGCCACCCUCUUCCCCCAGCACCACCAUGUCCAGAAAGUCCAGUGUCUGCAGCAGCCUGAACAGUGUCAACAGCAGUGACUCCCGGUCCAGCGGCUCCCACUCGCAUUCCCCCAGCUCACAUUACCGCUACCGCAGCUCCAACCUGGCCCAGCAGGCUCCUGUGAGGCUGUCCAGCGUGUCCUCCCAUGACUCAGGAUUCAUAUCCCAGGAUGCCUUCCAGUCCAAGUCACCAUCCCCCAUGCCGCCAGAGGCCCCCAACCAGUUGUCUAACGGGUUUUCUCACUAUAGUUUAUCAAGUGAGUCCCACGUGGGGCCCACGGGUGCAGGCCUUUUCCCUCAUUGCCUGCCUGCCUCCCGCCUGCUCCCUCGGGUCACCUCUGUCCACCUUCCAGACUACGCUCAUUAUUACACCAUUGGGCCCGGCAUGUUCCCGUCAUCUCAGAUCCCUAGCUGGAAGGACUGGGCUAAGCCUGGGCCCUAUGACCAGCCUCUGGUGAACACCCUGCAGCGCCGCAAAGAGAAGCGAGAACCGGACCCCAACGGGGGAGGACCCACUACCGCCAGCGGCCCACCUGCAGCAGCUGAGGAGGCUCAGAGACCACGGAGCAUGACUGUAUCGGCUGCCACCAGGCCUGGUGAGGAGAUGGAGGCUUGUGAGGAGCUGGCCCUGGCCCUGUCUCGGGGCCUGCAGCUGGACACCCAGAGGAGCAGCCGGGACUCGCUUCAGUGCUCCAGCGGCUACAGCACCCAGACAACCACCCCCUGCUGCUCUGAGGACACCAUCCCUUCCCAAGUUUCAGAUUAUGAUUAUUUCUCUGUAAGUGGUGACCAGGAGGCAGAUCAGCAGGAGUUCGACAAGUCCUCCACCAUUCCAAGAAACAGCGACAUCAGCCAGUCCUACCGACGGAUGUUCCAAGCCAAGCGUCCAGCCUCAACUGCUGGCCUCCCCACCACCCUGGGACCUGCUAUGGUCACUCCAGGGGUUGCAACUAUCCGACGGACCCCUUCCACCAAGCCUUCUGUCCGCCGGGGAACCAUUGGAGCUGGUCCCAUCCCCAUCAAGACACCCGUGAUCCCUGUCAAGACCCCAACCGUCCCAGACCUCCCAGGGGUGUUGCCAGCCCCUCCAGAUGGGCCAGAAGAGCGGGGGGAGCACAGCCCUGAGUCGCCAUCUGUGGGUGAGGGCCCCCAAGGUGUCACCAGCAUGCCCUCCUCAAUGUGGAGCGGCCAAGCUUCCGUUAACCCUCCACUUCCAGGCCCGAAGCCCAGUAUCCCUGAGGAGCACAGACAGGCAAUUCCAGAAAGUGAAGCUGAAGACCAGGAACGGGAACCCCCAAGUGCCACUGUCUCCCCAGGCCAGAUUCCAGAGAGUGACCCUGCAGACCUGAGCCCAAGGGAUACUCCACAAGGAGAAGACAUGCUGAACGCCAUCCGAAGGGGCGUGAAACUGAAGAAGACCACGACAAACGAUCGCUCAGCCCCUCGCUUUUCUUAGGUUCACAAGAAAUGCGCCGGUGGGGAAUGAACUGUUUCAUUAAUAAAACCUAAUUUGUCUUGAUCCAUUCCACUCUAUAAUAAAACAAAAGAUUUUGUAGGCAACUCGGAAUAUAGCUCUUUUGAAAGUACUCGACACCUUUAGAUAAGAAUUAAAACCAACCUAUGUAACUGACAUAAUCUUGAUCUUUUAAUUUGUAAAUAUUGACAAUUUUCUUUCUGCACAUUUUAAUCUUAGUUUCCCUUUUGAUUUUUCUGAAGGUGCCAAAUUCCAUUUAACUUUUUUACAAGUCUUUGUAAAAUUUUAAAUGCAUAAAGGGGGUUGGGGCAGGGGAACCACGAAGUAGUUAAUUUUAGAAAAGGAUUUACUAUACUUCACUCUUCUUUUUUUUUCCCCACAAGCUUUUGUAGAUGCAUUGUAGUAGUCUAGCUUAGAAGCAAAUGCAAGUUAUUUUAAUGUACAAACUAAAUGGGUAAGAGGUAAAAUCUUCAUUUAAAUAUACUAUGUUCUGGAUGAAAAGAGCAGGAGUAACAAUUGAUGAGCAAUAUUCAGAGUGAAGUAAAUCUGGAAAUGGUAGACUGUGUUGGGAUUGGGGGGAGGGCCAUGGGAGGGGUACAUCGUCAACAUAGCCGAUCCUGUUACAUUUAAGAGUAGCCUCGUAGGUUGAAUUUCUUCUGGUAGCUUCAUGGUAAAUGCAUCCGAAUAAGCCAUACUGGAUUGCAGUGUUUGUUUCUGUAGGGUGUUUAAGGACUUGACUUCCUUUCUCCCAUGAUUCCUCUGGACUGCACACAGCACCCACAACCAGCCCCAUGCAUGCUGCUGCCUCUGGGCAGUCGUAGAAUCUCCCACUUCAGUUUCUCGUUGAUUGUACUCACCUUUAUGGAAUCCAAAUACAUCCAAAAGGGUAAGGCAGUUUUAAAAAUGUGAAAACAUUUAAAAAUGAUAAUAGCAGGGAAUUCUUAGAUUAUAGUAAAUGCCUUUUACUUAACUGUGCCCAGCAGGCUGGGUGCGUUAAAAAGCCCAAGUAUUUUGAAAAAACUCGAACAGAUUUGACAAGGGUAGCCAGCUUGGAGUCUAGCAACUUGCCAAUGUGUUUACCAAUCUGGGGGCUUGUUUUUCUUUUCUUCUUUCAAAUAAAUGGCAGUUAACUGGCUUUACAGUAAACAUUGAAGAGAGGAGGAUUUGUUUAUUGUCACUGGGAAUCUGACCACUAUACUGUCCUUUUUUUGUAUUCUGGGUAAAUGUUUUUUGGAAAAGAUUUGUCUUUUCUAAGUGGAAGUUAAAUUUGUUAUACUGCCCAUCCCCUAAAGCCAACAGAGAUUUGUAGAUUUAAAGGGAUCACAUUUGAAGACAAUAGUGUUUAAGAAAGCAAGCAAGUCCCUUAGCAGUCAGGUCAUAACAGGGCACAUUUCUGACCGAACCCUCUCAAGGCAGAGGAGGAGUUUGGUGGGUUUCAUACACCCUGCAGAUUCCUGUUGGCUCUAACCCUCAAUUACCUAAUCUUAUGCUUUAACACAUAACUGCAUUGGAUGUGAGAGUAACGUACCGUAUGGUCAUUGUUCUAUAUAUUAACAUUGAACACUGCUGCGAUUGCUCAAGGACAUUUUAUGUUACGGCUUUAAAGCAAAGGCAUGAUUAUUAGAAACUAUUUAAGCUUUUUUCUUUGAAAAACAAGCUCCUUUUACAGAAUAUAAACAACAGUAGUGCCUGUGGUUUAGCCCACCAAUCUUGAUGACUAAAAGUAGCUGAUGCAUUGUGCAUAUGAUGCUUGAGAUGGUUUUUGCAAAAGCAGAAAUCGCUGCAAGGUAAUCACAAUAGAUAAAAGUGGUAUUUUAAACCUUUGAAAUAAAUGGAUGUAACUGUACCUUGGUACAGCUUUUCACUUGUUUAGUUUUUAAACGUUAGUAUAAUCUGAAUAAAUAAAAUGUUGCCAAAUUCAAUGUAGAAAGAAUGUGACAACACACCUUGGGUAGUUCUGCUUGUGUUUUUGCAUAUUGUAAAAGCAGUGUCACAGCUAAAAAGAAAGAAAUCGUUUCUAACAGUAAAUUAUUGUGCUUUAGUUGCUAGUUUGUACUGAGAGUUGACCUCUCCCUGUGCAGUUUUUUGUUCUAAACUUGUAUAAAUAACAAUUGUGUAAUGUGUCUCCCUCCUACAUUGUAACAAUUGCUUCAGCCUACGUUAUAAAUAAAGAACCACUAGAUUAAAAAA